AGUUUCCUACAGGCCCGGAAACGGAUCGCGUUGGGUGAAGGUGACGGCGUCGAGCGUGAGUGACCCUCUGUGUAGAUUAAACCUGCGCUCCCUGUUUCCCAUUUCCACAGCCGAUGUCCAGGGUCGAUACGGCCCUUAAAAUCCCCGUACACUCCACCCCAGGACCUCUCUGACCUCAUCUCCUGCCUGUGUCCUCCUCGCUCCCUCUGCUCCAGCCAAGCAUGCGUCCUUCCUGUUCCUGGGCCGAGCUUGCUCCUGCCUCAAGGCCUUCACGUGGGCUGUGCCUCUGCUGGAACUCGCUGGCCCCUCAGCUGCAGAAAGGUGGGAGACAAUGCCUUGGAGCUGCAAAUCUUCUCUGAGUCUGAAGCAUCCUGCCUGACGCGUUUGCUCACAUUGACCCGUGCCUUCCCUCAGUCCUUCUCAUCUCUACUGAGAUUCCGUCUCACCCUGACCCUGUGACAUGAACUUCUGAAGAGUCCACUGGGCAUGGUCCUGGGAAGGGCUCACACCCAGACAUGGAUGGAGACGGGUUGACAUUCAGGGACGUGGCCAUCGAAUUCUCUCAAGAUGAGUGGAAAUGCCUGAACUCUACACAGAGGACUUUAUACAGGGAUGUGAUGUUGGAGAACUACAGGAACCUGGUCUCCCUGGAGUAUUAUCCUAUGUGGGAGCACAGGAAAGAGCCCUGGACCAUAGAAAGCCAAGUACGAGUAGCAAGAAAACCAAAAGGGUGGGAAUGGAUCAAAGGUGUGAAAACAGGCUGGAGUGCAAUGGUGCAAUCUCGGCUCACUGCAACCUUCGCCUCCCGGAUUCAAAUGAUUCUCCUGCCUCAGCCUCCCGAGUAGCUGGGAUUACAGAUCUGUCUCGUAACUGUGUAAUCAAGGAACUAGCACCACAACAGGAAGGUAACCCAGGAGAAGUAUUCCACACAGUGACAUUGGAACAACAUGAAAAACAUGACAUUGAAGAGUUUUGCUUCAGGGAAAUCAAGAAAAAAAUACACGACUUUGACUGUCAGUGGAGAGAUGAUGAAAGAAAUUGCAACAAAGUGACUACGGCCCCAAAAGAAAAUCUUACUUGUAGGAGAGACCAACGCGAUAGAAGAGGUAUAGGAAACAAGUCUAUUAAACAUCAGCUUGGAUUAAGCUUUCUACCACAUCCCCAUGAACUGCAGCAGUUUCAAGCUGAAGGGAAAAUUUAUGAAUGUAACCAUGUUGAGAAGUCUGUCAACCAUGGUUCCUCAGUUUCACCACCCCAAAUAAUUUCUUCUACCAUCAAAACCCAUGUUUCUAAUAAAUAUGGGACUGAUUUCAUCUGUUCUUCAUUACUCACACAAGAACAGAAAUCAUGCAUUAGGGAAAAACCUUACAGAUAUAUUGAGUGCGACAAAGCCUUGAAUCAUGGCUCACACAUGACUGUACGUCAGGUAAGUCAUUCUGGAGAGAAAGGAUAUAAAUGUGAUCUGUGUGGCAAGGUCUUUAGUCAAAAAUCAAACCUUGCGCGUCAUUGGAGAGUUCAUACUGGAGAGAAACCAUACAAAUGUAAUGAAUGUGACAGAAGUUUCAGUCGCAACUCAUGCCUUGCACUACAUCGGAGAGUUCACACUGGAGAGAAACCUUACAAAUGUUAUGAGUGUGACAAGGUCUUCAGUCGAAAUUCAUGCCUUGCACUACAUCAGAAAACUCAUAUUGGAGAGAAACCUUACACAUGUAAAGAGUGUGGCAAAGCCUUUAGUGUGAGGUCAACACUUACCAACCAUCAGGUAAUUCAUAGUGGCAAGAAACCUUACAAAUGCAAUGAAUGUGGCAAGGUGUUCAGUCAGACUUCAAGCCUUGCAACUCAUCAGAGAAUUCACACUGGGGAGAAACCAUACAAGUGUAAUGAAUGUGGUAAAGUCUUCAGUCAGACUUCAAGCCUUGCAAGGCAUUGGAGAAUUCAUACUGGAGAGAAACCUUACAAAUGCAAUGAAUGUGGUAAGGUUUUCAGUUACAAUUCACACCUUGCGAGUCAUCGGAGAGUUCAUACUGGAGAGAAACCUUACAAGUGUAAUGAGUGUGGGAAAGCCUUUAGUGUGCAUUCGAACUUAACUACCCAUCAGGUCAUCCAUACUGGAGAGAAGCCUUACAAAUGUAAUCAAUGUGGCAAAGGCUUCAGUGUGCAUUCAAGCCUAACUACCCAUCAGGUCAUCCAUACUGGAGAAAAACCUUACAAAUGUAAUGAGUGUGGCAAAUCCUUUAGUGUGCGCCCAAACCUCACUAGACAUCAGAUAAUCCAUACUGGAAAGAAACCUUACAAAUGUAGUGAUUGUGGGAAGUCCUUUAGUGUGCGCCCAAACCUCUUCAGACAUCAAAUUAUCCAUACUAAGGAGAAACCUUAUAAAAGAAAUUAAUAUGGCAAGGUCUUCAGUCAAAGUUUAAAUCCUGUGAGUCAUCAAAGAAUUUAUAUCAGAGAGAAACCAUACAAGUAUAAUAAAUGUGGCAAGGUUUUCAGUCACAAUUCACUCCUACACAGCAUCAGAGAAUUUCAUUCUUGAGAGAAUCCUUACGAGUACAGCAAACCCUUCAUCACAAGUUCAAGCAUUCAUUGACAUCAGAGUCCAUGCUAAAGAGAAAUCAUAUACACCUAACUGUGUGGCAGAGGCUUCAUUUAGGUCUCACAACUCACUAGACAUCAAAAUGUGUAAACAUCUUUGUAUAUUUUGUGCAUGUUGAAGCUAUUAACCAAGGAUCAAAACUGUAACACAUCCAAGGAUUUAUGUGAGGAAUAAUUCAGUCUAGUUGUGCUGAUAAACUUUUCAUAUUACACAUUGUAGAACAAAUGCAAGCCCAAAUAUGUUAAAACUCACACAACAUGAUAUAUAUUAAAGGUUGCAGGAUGUUUGAAGUCA